AGCUAACGGAUGUGGCAUGGGGCGGGGGACCAGGCCGGAGGCGGGCUGCCGGGAGGGGGGAUUCCCUCGUGCCCCAAGGGCGAAUCUCAGGUCGGAGGAAGGGGCUGAGGGGAUUCCCUCUCCCACCGGGUCCGACUCUUCGCUCCCCAAGCCGCGGAGGGCCAGCCUCUUCUUCGGCGCCCUCCAGGCCUGUUGGAGGCCCCCCCAGGAUGCAAUGGCGCAGCCCCCCCGGCUGAGCCGCUCUGGUGCCUCCUCACUUUGGGACCCAGCUUCUCCUGCUCCCACCUCUGGCCCCAGGCCUCGGCUUUGGGAGGGUCAAGAUGUGCUGGCCAGAUGGACUGAUGGGCUGCUAUACUUGGGUACCAUCAAAAAGGUGGACAGUGCUAGGGAGGUGUGUCUGGUCCAGUUUGAGGAUGAUUCGCAGUUUCUGGUUCUAUGGAAAGACAUUAGCCCUGCUGCCCUCCCUGGAGAGGAACUCCUCUGUUGUGUCUGUCGCUCUGAGACUGUGGUCCCUGGGAACCGGCUGGUCAGCUGUGAGAAGUGUCGCCAUGCUUAUCACCAGGACUGCCAUGUUCCCAGGGCUCCAGCCCCUGGAGAGGGAGAGGGCACAUCCUGGGUAUGCCGCCAGUGUGUCUUUGCGAUCGCCACCAAGAGGGGAGGUGCCCUGAAGAAGGGCCCCUAUGCCCGGGCCAUGCUGGGUAUGAAGCUUUCUCUGCCAUAUGGACUGAAGGGGCUGGACUGGGAUGCUGGACAUCUGAGCAACCGACAGCAGAGUUACUGUUACUGUGGUGGCCCUGGGGAGUGGAACCUGAAAAUGCUGCAGUGCCGGAGCUGCCUGCAGUGGUUCCAUGAGGCCUGCACCCAGUGUCUGAGCAAGCCCCUCCUCUAUGGGGACAGGUUCUAUGAAUUUGAAUGCUGUGUGUGUCGCGGGGGCCCUGAGAAAGUCCGGAGACUACAGCUUCGCUGGGUGGAUGUGGCCCAUCUUGUCCUGUAUCACCUCAGUGUUUGCUGUAAGAAGAAAUACUUUGAUUUUGAUCGUGAGAUCCUCCCCUUCACUUCUGAGAAUUGGGACAGUUUGCUCCUGGGGGAGCUUUCAGACACCCCCAAAGGAGAACGUUCUUCCAGGCUCCUCUCUGCUCUUAACAGCCACAAGGACCGUUUCAUUUCAGGGAGAGAGAUUAAGAAGAGGAAAUGUUUGUUUGGUCUCCAUGCUCGGAUGCCUCCCCCUGUGGAGCCCCCUACUGGAGAUGGAGCACUCACCAGCUUCCCUUCAGGGCAGGGCCCUGGGGGAGGGGUCUCACGUCCCCUGGGGAAGCGCCGGAGGCCGGAGCCAGAGCCCCUGAGGAGGAGGCAGAAGGGGAAAGUGGAGGAGCUGGGGCCACCCUCAGCAGUGCGCAAUCAGCCCGAGCCCCAGGAGCAGAGGGAGCGGGCUCAUCUGCAGAGGGCACUGCAGUCCUUUGCCCCCUCUUCUAGGCCUCAGUGUCUCCACCAUCCCCCAGCCCUAACCAGAGUUACCAGGGCAGCAGCGGCUACAACUUCCGGCCCACAGAUGCCCGCUGCCUGCCCAGCAGCCCCAUCCGGAUGUUUGCUUCCUUCCACCCUUCUGCCAGCACCGCAGGGACCUCUGGGGACAGUGGACCCCCAGACAGGUCACCCCUGGAACUUCACAUUGGUUUCCCCACAGACAUCCCUAAAAGUGCCCCCCACUCGAUGACUGCCUCAUCUUCCUCAGUUUCAUCCCCAUCCCCAGGUCUUCCUAGACGCUCAGCACCCCCUUCUCCCCUGUGCCGUAGUUUGUCUCCUGGGACUGGGGGAGGAGUCCGAGGUGGGGUUGGUUACCUGUCCCGAGGGGACCCUGUCCGGGUCCUUGCUCGGAGAGUACGGCCUGAUGGCUCUGUGCAGUACCUGGUUGAGUGGGGAGGAGGGGGCAUCUUCUGAACAGCCUGCCUCUGCCCAGCUCCCCAUUCACACACACCGGCACUUUCAUACCCUGACCUCUGACCUCACCUACAGCUGGGAUGUACCUGGAGAGAUAGGGGGUAGUUCUCCCUACUGCCCAGGCUGGAAUCCAAGAGUGGGGAGUGGGGAAGAGGCCCUCUUCUCUACCCUCCUUCAUGAUUCCUGACCCCUCCCAUCCUUCCCAUUUCCUUUGAUGUUAUUUUGUUACAGCUUUUUAAAUAUUUUUUAAAAUUAUUUAACCCCUGGGGGCAGAGACUGAGGAGGGAGGAUGAUAAGGGAUCCCGGACUCUGUAUGAUUGAAAUAAAGAGAAAUAAACAAA